AGUGCCUGCGAGCUCCGCUGCUGCUUGGGGAAUUCACUUUGCUGCUUGUUCGCUUCUCCCUUCCUCAGGCUUCUUCUGAUGGUUUUCCGUCUCCUGCCCGAGCCUUUCCUUUAAAAGGAAAACUUUACUGCGAUACCCUUUUCCCCUUGGAGGAGAGGAUUAAAAGUUCCAAGAACUGGUGCCGCCCGUGCCAUUUGGGCGCUGGGAAGGUGCUCGGCGGCGGGGUUCCCGGUCCCACCAUGUGCACCAACAUAGUUUACGAGUGGCUCAAAGCGCUGCAGCUUCCGCAGUACGCGGAGUCCUUCGUGGAUAACGGCUACGAUGACCUGGAGGUGUGCAAGCAGAUCGGGGACCCGGACCUGGAUGCCAUCGGGGUGCUGGCGCCCGCGCACCGCCGCCGUAUCCUGGAGGCCGUGCGCCGGCUGCGGGAGCAGGACGCCAACGCCGCCGGCCUCUACUUCACGCUUGAGCCGCAGCCGGCGCCCCCCGGGCCGCCCGCCGACGCCGUCCCCACCGGCCGCCGGGGGGAGCCGUGCGGCGGCCCGGCCCAGGGCACCCGCGGGGACUCUCGCGGCCACACGACCGCCCCCCGCAGCAGGGAGCUGGUGAGCUACCCCAAACUGAAGCUGAAGAUCAUGAUCAGGGAUAAGCUCGUCCGUGACGGCAUCCACCUGAGCAAGCCCCCGUACUCCCGCAAGGUAAGUGGUGUUUUAUCUUCAUUGCUUCAGGGAGUGUUGAUUUGUCUGGUAAGUGUUCGUUUUGCUCUGGUACAAGGUACUACUUCAAAGAUGCAUGUGAAUUGCCUGUGAGAACCAAAAGGCAAACCAGAAAGCAUAAGCGAACUUUGGAAAUGAUAUACACUGAGAAGGCUGGUGUGUGUUCAAUCUUGUUCAGAUUUUUUCUUUUUUCUGAGAGCUUACUUUGGAGUUACAACACACUUUGUUCUUCGGUCUGGAAAAGAGCCCAGGGGCUGAUUAAGUGUUGAUGAAAACUUGCCUUCCAUAAAUUCUUUUUAUGUGAAUUUUCUUGUCUUUUUUUCUUUUACUUCUUUCUGCCUUUAUUGGAAUUUUUUAAAUGCCCUCCAUUCAGAUUUUGAUAAAACCAUAAAACUCCAGAUAGAGGCAUUUUGCUGAAGUUUUUGCUACUUACGUAUACUGUGUUACUCCAGUAUUUUGACUAAAUUGUUACCCAGAACCUCCUUUGCUUUUCUGUUCUCCUCCUCCUGUGUCACGGUGGUUUCAUCUGUACGGUAUUAAUGUUCCAUUGGUACUCAGCACAAUGUGGCGAUUAAGUCCUACUUCUCAAUAACAUUUUUAUUAAGCUACUGAAACAAAUAUGUCCCUAAAUUUCUAGCUGUACUGGCACAGACAUUAUUUUACUGAUUCCUUCUAUAAAUUAGUGACUGAGAGUUGCUGUUUUUCUAGAUAUGUUGUUGAUACCGAGAUUUUUUCCUUUAAAAGAAUUACCAAGGAGCUAUCCAGGAUGAAGAUGAAUUGCAAGGAGAGAAAAAAAAAAAAACACGAAUCAUUUGAUCUGUGAAUUUCAUAGUUGAAUAUACCCAACAUCUGAUGAUUUUAUUUUGUUUCUUAUAAUAGUGGACUCUCCCACUUUUUUGAGCUGACACAGAAAAUGCUAGACCACAUUGUCUUUUGAAAGGAAUAUAGGAAAUUCCAUUUCCCUGUGUGUAAUAUCUAUAGACCUUUGUUAUCUUACGUUAUAGGUUCAGAUUAUUGGUUCCGUUAGAAGUAAUUGUUCUUUAAAAGCAUUGAAUUUGGUUUAGCUAUAUUCUGCUGUCCUCUCCUUCACGUUCAUCAUCCCCCAAAAUUUUGCCAUUACAUUAAUAAAUUUAGCUGAGAUAUAUCUAUAUCUAUAUCUGUAUAGUUAGGUGCUUAAAGAGGUUUUUAUUUUAAAUAUACAUUGGAUCUAUUUGCCUUUUGGGGGAAGGGUUCUUUUUUGGUUUUUUGUUUUGUUUUGUUUUGAUUUUUGCUUUUGAUCAUCUGAGCUUAAAAUGUUUUACUUGUGUUUAUGUGUGUUUAAUAGAACAUGUUUGAAGAAGAGUCCCCAGAGGUCAACUAAACUGCUCUUGAAACGUUCAAAAGACGCAGACAUUGCUUUAAAUAACCCAUAUGGGAUUUUGACCCCAUGCUGUUUGCAGUCCUGCAAUAGAAUUUUUCUAUUAAAGAUUCUGGAUUAAAAAGAUCAGAAAACAGGAGACAGAAAGAUGGAGGGGUGAAGAAGGUUAGAUUUCAAACUUGCAUAGGCUUUUCCCCAGACUUUGAAGCCUAUCAGAGACCCACAGACGUGUGAACCAAGACAUUAUUUGAACAGCCUGCUUAACAACAGGCUGAAUAGAGAACCACAUUUUAAAUUGACAAAGUUAGCCCGUGCUGAGAGUUUUUUAUUAUUUGCCUUUGACCUUAUUGGACACUGUAAAUGAAAUAUAGUGGUGCAGGUUUGAAAAGGCCAGGGGCUACUUAGUUAUGCCACUCCUAUGAUGGGGGAAAAAACCCAAGAGUGAACAAAUACAGUAUAUUUAACUCUAUCCCCUUAACUCAGACCGCAGUAAUAUAAAUGGUUCCAAUCUGUAACCCCAGUUUGGUAAGAAAUCUUUUGUUAUUUUUAAAUUCAUUUCACUAUAUUCAGGUAAGCCACACAGAAAAGUCAAAGCUGGAGAGGGGGCUGAGUUUUAUUUUCACUAUAAAGAGAACUUGAAAACACUUUAUUUGGGAUAAAGUCUAUUUUUAACUUAGGUUUCCUAAUUUCUAUCACGCUACUUCUAAUGCUUCUACAUGCUACUUACUGCCACUCUAAAAUCAGAUGCACUAGAGUUUCUGCCAGCAAACUUAUCUAAAAUAUCGUUAUUUUUCUUAUUAAAAAAUGUCAGUCUAGUUAUCUGUAACAUACAAUGACCACACUGGAUUUCCACUCCUGGGUAAAAGCAACUAUAUGAUUAUAUAAGUGACAAUUGUACAACGCUCAUUUCUAUAUUGUUUGAGAACUCUUAUGUGAUAUGGAUAACUAAAAGAUACUAUACUUCCUCAACAUUAAAUUUUUAAUUCUAUUAGGUUCAUUUUGUUAUACUGCAUUUCUUAAAUAAUUCAAGUAUGAUAAAAUAUAUUGUAGAAUUGGACUGAAUUAUGAAAUGCAUUGUAAUUAAUUUCUUUCCUCUAGUGACUUGUGUUAGUACUUUGCUGAUAAUAAGAAAUAUGAUGUAUCCUGAACCUCAUGAAGAUACAAUGUUAGAGCAGAAGGUAUAAGACAUGUCAGGCACUUCAAAAAACAGAUAGAAAACCAAGACGGAAUAUGAAGCCUGGAAUAGAAAACAAGCAUCUUAGGAGAAGGGAAGGCAUUGAAAUUUUCACGCAGUUAGCCGUGCAGAGAAAACACAGUUUAUUUUUCUAUGACUAAUAUGAUCAUUUUGCAUUCUUACCAUACCAGAUGGGAGAAAUUGGGAUUUGCUUUUUAAUAUAUCUCAAUCUCUUCUCAUUUAAACCAUCUUCUGUCAUCCUGAAAAAGUAGGCAAAGCUUAACUUCCUGUAGGUUCUGGCUGAAGAGUAUCUGCUCUGCCUAUCUGCAGCCCCCAGCCUCAGCAUGGCCUCCUGAUAUUGGGCUGGUUCACAUGUGUGCACUAGCUGGGACCCACUCAGCUGCAUCAAGGUUUGUGCGUGGCAUUCAGACUGCUGCUGUGAACUGUGGUUUUGCCUCUCCUGGCUUGAUACGUCCUCCUGAGGUCUAGCUAACUCACAUUUGGCCCCGACCUGGUAUGACCACCCUCACCCUGUACCCAGGCUGUCAGGGACAGUUCAUGCUGGGAAGUUCACAGCCAGCACAACCUUCUCCUCCUUCCUAAUGGGCACAGUGGAAACCUGGGCCAUCUCCCCAAAGCAGCAGGGUAAGCUCAGGUGUUGGGGACCUUAAGUUUCCUCACUGAAUCCAAACGUUUGGACCUCCCACAUUCUUCCAGGCACUCUUGGAAACAGUCUGUUCCCGAAAACCCAAACAGGAAGCAGGCUGAAAUCCUCCUCACCCUCAAUAUUGCUCUCAGCCAAAUUUCACAAUCCUGCCUGCCAAGAUUUUGAAAUAGAGAGGGGAGGUCAAGUUUUCUUUCUCUGUUUCCCUCGCCUCCACAUCUUUCUCUUCCCACCGUCGUUCUGGAAGGGUGUUCUGCUUUCUUUACCUCAUAUUCUAGACCUUUCUACUCAGGCCAUGUAAUAAAUUCUAAGAUCUAGUAGCCAGGCUUGGCUCUCCAUGUGCUAAGUGAGAGCAAAUAGGACUUAAAAAAAUUUUUCUCCCUCAAUUCUGACCUUUAUGACUGUUAACCCAACUCCAGGAUUCUAUUUGGUCAUCAAAGACCAAACUGACCCUUUCUUUUCACCUUUCCUUGUUUCUUGUUUCUUUUCUUUCUUUCUUUCUUUCUUUUUUUUUUUAUGACGGAGUCUCGCUCUGUCGCCAGGCUGGAGUGCAGUGGCGCGAUCUCGGCUCACUGCAAGCUCCGCCUUCCGGGUUCACGCCAUUCUCCUGCCUCAGCCUCCCACGUAGCUGGGACUACAGGAGCCCACCAACACGCCCGGCUAAUUUUUGUAUUUUUAGUAGAGACUGGGUUUCACCGUGUUAGCCAGGAUGGUUUCGAUAUCCUGGCCUCGUGAUCCACCCGCCUUGGCCUCCCAAAGUGUCUUUUCUUUCAUUUCUACCAUCACAGCCCUAAUGCCCUUUCUAUACCAGACAGGUCAGUGCAUUGGGCUCACAAAUGAGCAACUCAAGUACACAGAAAUGCAAACGAGAGAAGCACAUCAAAAUGUGUCUACCGCACUGCGUGUCCUUCAAGGAGAUUGGUGUGGGUUCCAGGGGAUUGUGUGUUUGAUCAGCAAAAAAAUAAAAAUGAUAUUUAUUUUAUUUGGUGGCUUAUGUCAGGGGCAUAGAGAAAGGCUGGGGCUAGACUUAAGGGGAAUUUGAUUGAUUGGCCAAAGGCUUCAGUCAUAUAGAGCCACAGUCCCAAAGUGAUUUCGGCAAAGCAGUCAUUCCGUAAGAUGUUCUGACAGACGCAGAAUAAAUGUAUUUGGGAUUGCUACAUACCAUAUGGCCCCUCUUAAGACUCUUAAUGUGUAUUAGCAUAGUAAUGUUUCAGAUAAUUCCUGCCACAUCGGGAUACAUAGAACACCAUUUAACGCAGGGGGGCCAUAUUCAUGUAACACCUAUUAACAAUCGAGAAAUCUUUCCCUUGAGAACUGCUGCUAGUGUAAUGAUGAAGCUAGAAAUUGGUUUUGGUGAGAACCAACAGGAGGGAAGUAGAGCUUUAGGAAGUUCUUUCAGUUUUUAUUCAGAGUAAGAGGGCUUACUCUGUCCAAGGCACGCUGAUUAAUCAGUCCAAAAAGAUGAAUGCCAAAUCGGUGCUUGAGGACUCAGAAUUUCCCAAAAUUGCCAUCUUUAUGUGUAAGUAUAGAAUGUCAGCUAUUUACAGUCAGUUUGCUAUGCAGUACCAGUAAAAUACUCUGCUUGUAUUUGAUAUAUCAAGAUUAUUAAAGAAAUUACCAACCUUCCCCCAAAAUAAUUGUUUUUAGUGAACAGCUAAUGUUAUUUCCUUUGCUGGGUAGGCGUGAUAUAUUAAUGGUGAUGGAUAUCAAUUGUGUAUCAAUGGAGAUGAAUGAAUGUCAACACUUUGAACAUACUAUCAAGGUAUUCCAAAAUAUUUUUAUGGUAAUAUUGCUGAAACUAAGCCUUUUUUGGUGAUCUUUGUUUUUGUUUGUUUGUUUGUUUCGAGACAGAGUCUCGCUCUGUCACCCAGGCUGGAGUGCAGAGACGUGACCUCAGCUCACUGCAAGCACUGCCUCCCAGGUUCAAGUGAUUCUCCUGCCUCAGCCUCCCUAGUAGCUGGGAUUACAGGCAUGCACCACCACACCCGCGAAUUUUUUUUGUACUUUUUGUAGAGAUGGGGUUUUGCCAUGUUGGCCAGGCUAGUCUUGAACUCCUGACUUUCAAGUGAUCCUCCCGCCUUGGCCUCCCAAACUGCUGGGAUUACUGGCGUGAGCCACCGCACCCGGCCCUUUUUUGAUGAUCUUUGAAAGAACCUAUAUGAAAUAAAACUUGGAGAGACCUACAUUUCAUUUCAUAAUGUAUUAUCUCCUUUUUUAAUUGAAAAUAUUACAACUUUCUAUGUUAAUCAUGAUAAAAUGCCUCAGAGGACUUUUUAUAUUUUAUACAGCUUGACCAAUUUUAUGUUUUAAUUUUUAAUUUUUUCUCCUUCCUUCAUAUAGUAUUCUUUUUUAAUGUGCCUUUAUCCUCACUGAAUACCCUGACAUAUUCAAAACCUCCUACAGUUGAUGUCAGUAAUACUAAGCGUCAAGAUCUCCAAAUUCAUCUAAUUCCAGUUUACUUUGUCAAUAAUCCUUGUCCUCUUUUCAAAAGUGUGGCAUAUUUUGAAAAAUAAUCAGAUAUUUUUAAAUCCGUGUAAAACAGGAGAGUCCACUGUAAAUCUUUGCUUUACCAAAGGUGGUUUAUUCAGCUACAAUUUCUCUCAUUUUGGUUUUUUUUUUUCUCUUUCUUCCUUUGGCCACUUCAGCCAUUCGACUCUCAGAAAUUCUGUCAGGAAAAAUAAAUGGAUAUGAAAUCUGAAGAUAAAGGUUUGUGGGGAAAGAAUAAAAGGAUCAUGAAAUGUCAGGGCUGAAAAAUAUCUUAGCAUCCAGCCUAGUGUUCUAUUUACACCAUCCCUGUUUUGGCUCCCAAUCUGAUUCUCUUCCUAUUGCAUCAAACUGAGUUUUAAAGAAAUUUGAAACUAUGCAUUUCAAGACUAUUUGGUGAUUAUGUUAAUCUCCAAUUCUGCCUAUUUUUGAUUAUGUUAAAAUCAGCCAAAAUAUAGAACAUAGAGUUAUGCUUAUGCCCAACAUCAUAAUAUGCCUUCAGUUAUUAACAUAUGUUGUAGGUAAGCUUGUUAUUAUUUGAAAUGUAAAUAUUUAUAUGUGUAAUGUGUAAAAGUUUUCAAAUAUGGGUCAUAACAUAUCCAAUGGUUUAUUUGUCUAUGCCACUAAUACAUCUUUGGGCACCCAAGUUUAAGUGCAGUACAUUUUGCUGGUUGAUGUACCAAGGAAUGACUUAUAAUUGUGAUGAAAUUUGAACUUCAUAUUGCAAAAGAUAAUCAUCAUUUGCUAGAAAAAAUUAAAACCGUUUAAAUUUUUAUCAUAGAAAGAGCUAAAAGAAAUUCUAAGUAUAUUUUUAUAGAUGAGCCACUUUGGAAAUUUCACAGAUAAAACACCAGCUUGUUAACAGAGUUAAGCUACCAAAAAGACACUCCAGAAUGGGCCGUAACAUAACUUUUUACCAGUGUAACUUACACUGUGAUUUAAAAGUGUGUAUGUGGUCAAAUAUGUUUCCUUUGUUUUCACUGAAGUAUUUUUAUUCAGUAAAUACAGUCAUUAUUUUAUCACCUUCGUGUUUUAAGCUCGAAUUGUAUUGAAUCACAUUUAGUAAGUAAAAUAAUCUAUACUCCUGCAAUUCUGAAAGUGAUUCAAAUCCAUUUUAGGAUACCAGAUUGAAAAACAGCAACUUAAUGUUGAGAUAACGUCAUGGGGUGCACAGUGAUAUUUUGAUCAGCAAUGGACCACAUAUAGGAUAGCGGUGGUCCCAUCAGAUUACAAUGGAGCUGAAAAUUUCUUAUCUCCUAGUGACACGGUAGCCAUUGGAACAUUAUAGCAUACUUUAUUUUUAUAAAUUUAUUGUGGCCUAAGUGUAAGGUGUUUUUAAAACCUAUGGGAGUGUACGCUAAUGUCCUAGGCCUUCGCAUUCACCCAUCACUCACUGACUCAGCCAAAGUAACUUCCAGUCCUGCUAGCUCCAUUCGUGGUAAGUGCCCUGUACAUGUUUACCAUUUUUAACCUCUUUUUUUUUUUUUUUGAGACAGAGUCUCGCUCUGUCGC